AGUACUUCUUGGACAUGAGGGUGUUUACCGUCGUGCCUAAUUACGCGGGUUGGGAAUCUGAGAUACAGGGAAGGGCAGCGGCUGGCCCUGGGUCGGUCAGAUAAAUUAAGACAAAAGCAGGACCAGGCAUCGAUUAUUUUCUCCUGCUCAUCCCUUUCACGGAGGAAUUCUAAGCCCCGACACACUGUAUGACCUAAAGCCAGUCUCUGCCUGUCGCUGGGCCUCAGUUCGCCUGUCCUAAGUUUAAUUCAGAUUAUCUGGCACUCCUGGUCGGCUCCCUCAGCCGCUCAAAGCUGAUUGUACCCUUAUAAUAUGAAGACACUGAGGCUCAGAGAGGUUAAGUGACUCAGCCAAGGUCAAACAGCUAGUAAGUGGUGGAGCCAGGACUCAAAGCCAGUCUAGGAGCCAUGUCCACUUUGUUCCCCUCACUCUUCCCUCGUGUGACUGAGACUCUGUGGUUUAAUCUGGAUCGACCCUGUGUGGAAGAGACAGAGCUGCAGCAGCAGGAACAGCAGCAUCAGGCCUGGCUCCAAAGCAUCGCGGAGAAAGACAACAACCUGGUUCCUAUUGGCAAGCCAGCCUCAGAGCACUAUGAUGACGAGGAAGAAGAGGAUGAUGAAGAUGAUGAGGAUAGUGAAGAGGACUCAGAGGAUGAUGAGGAUAUGCAGGACAUGGACGAGAUGAAUGACUACAAUGAGUCACCGGAUGAUGGAGAGGUCAAUGAGGGAAGUCUGGAAGGCCAGUGUGGUGGAGGCGGCAGCGGUAGCGGCCACAGCUCUUAGCAUACUGCAAGAAGCGGGGUGCACCAGGGAAGAGCACAUGGUCAGCCAGCACGGUGGCACCUGCUGGCAGUAGGGCAUGGGCCUCCAGCAGCUGCAGGUCCCUCAGGUAACAUCGUGGCCGGUGUGCCAGGAGCACCAGGUCUGCCCGACUCAGCUGAUACUGGGUGCGUAGGCACGGGAUCACGUCCUCUGAGCUGCCCACGAUGAGCUCCACCUGUGGGGAUAGGGGGAGCUGGAGGUGAGGGUGGGGGGAAUUGUUCUCCCAGUCAAGACCCCACCAGGAUCUGGCUUACUUCAUGCCAGGUCCUGGCUUAGCUUCCCAUGAGUGUUCUCACAUUUCCUCUGACCUCAGAACCUAAGAAGUCAGGAUCAGUAUUGUGAUUUCCAUUCUGAAGAAGCUAAGGUUCAGAGGAUGCAUGCUUUGCUCAAGGUCACGUAGCUAACAAGAGGCAGAGUAAGAGCUGGACCCAAAUUUGCUGGGUUCCAGAGACCUUCCUCUUAGCUGUUUCUUUCGUCAUCCGGCAGAAAAUAAUGUGCAGAUGACUUGGGACAGGAGGGCAGGAGCUCACACACCAUCCAGCAUCACAGUCCCCAGAGUGGAGGUGCUUCCUUCUCCUUAGAUGGGAGUCCUUCACAAGGGAUGUCUGGGGGCAAGGCCUGGGGUGACAAAAAUCUGGGUUGGGGAGAUGGGAGGCUGACCAUGUGCUCAUCAAAGCCGGCCAGGCGGAUGAGUUUUUCAGCCACUGCUGCCGUGCGUGGGUCCCGCUCCACAGUAAGAAGGCGACCCCCAGGGGGCAGGGCUCGGGCAAUAAGCAGGGUAGAGUAUCCACAGUAGGUUCCCAAUUCCAGCACACAAGCAGGGGCCUUCUCCUCCACCAGCCGCAUCAGGAUCUGACCUAUGAGGGGAGAUGGCUGUUGCAGAAGACAUGGGAGAUGGAUGCAGGGCCCCUGAUAAAAGAUAUCUCAAAUGCCUACCUGCCUCACUGCAGCUCCCAACCAGCCGGGGUCUCAUCUGUCUCUUGUACCAUAGCCCCAGCUGCCCUCCUGGUCCCCGUCUCCUACAGUGUAGUCUUCACACCAGCCCUGGAAUCUUUCCAACAAAUCUGACCUUAUUACUCCUUGGCUCCUGUGAGCUGAAGGCCUUUGGGAUUGAACUUGGGAUUCUCAGCCUGGCAUUCAGGACCUUGGACCUGAUCCUAUCCUACCUUUCCAGGUUCAUCUCUCAGUACUUCCCACCUGUGGCCUGUAUCACAGCCAUCCCAAACAACUGUGCCCAGAAUCCAUCAAGCUGUCUCAUUCCUUCAUGCCACAUGUGUAUAUGUGGCUGGCUUUGCCCUUCCCACCCCCAUCGCCAUCUGCCUGGCCAACUCAGAACUUCCAGAUUCAGUUCAAAUGUUGCUCUUUCUCCAUGAAGUCCCAGGCAGAAACAACCACCCUAUCUUUCAGAUUUAUGAAAGGUCUCUGUUAGAAUUUGUAGUUUCAUUCCCCUUUUAUUGCUCAUCAAAUGUAUUUCUGAUCUUGGAAUUGGAUGAACUUUUAUUUAUUUAUUUUUGAGACCAAGUCUUGCUGUGUUGCCCAGGCUGGAGUGCAGUAGCAUGAUCACGGCUCACUGCAGCCUUGACCACCCAGGCUCAGGCAAUCCUCCCACCUCAGCAUUUCCAGUAGCUGGAACCACAGUUACUCACCACCACACCCGGCUAAUUUUUAAAUUUUUUGUAGAAACGGGGGUCUUGCUUUGUUACCCAGGCUAGUCUCGAACUCCUGGGCUCAAGUGAUCCUCCUGCUUUGGCCUCCCAAAGUGCUGGGAUUACAGGCAUGAGCCACCAUGCCCAGCCAGUGAAUUUCUUUUCUUUUCUUUUUCUUUUUUUUUUUUUUUUUGAGACAGGUUCUUGCUCUGUCACCCAUGCUGGAGUGCAGUGGCACAAUCACAGCUCACUGCAGCCUCAGCCUCCUGGGCUCAAGCAAUCCUCCCACCUCAGCCUCCCAAGUAGCUGGGACCACAGGCAUGUGCCACCAUGCCUGGGUAAUUUUUGUAUUUUUUGUAGAGAUGGGUUUUUGCCAUGUUGCCCAAGCCGGUCUCAAACUCCUGAGCUCAAGCAAUCUGCCCACCUCGGCCUCUCAAAGUGCUGGGAUUACAGGCACCAGCCACCACACAGCCGAAUUUCUUAAAUAAGACCCUAAAAGCACUUAUGCUGGGAUUGAGAUAAAUCCAGGCAGACAGCUACCCUAAAUGGUAUGUGGAAGCCUCCAUGGUGGAGAGGAAAGAUGUGGAGACAGAUAAUUACAAAGCUAUGGGUUAUCUGCUGAGAUGGUUAUUCCACUGUGUAUUAUGGUUCCUUUGAGGCCAGCAUUUGUGGCUCAUUCAUCUCUGUGGCCUCUACCCCUCUCCCUGGCACCUAGCACAUUCCUAAUACAAAAGAGGUGGCAAUAAAUGUUUGCUGAAUAAA